GCUGAGUGAGUGUGGGGGAUGGGGGGAGUGCCCAGCCUGCCUCCACCUGUGGUGUGCGCAAGAAUCAAGCACUUUAUUUGGUACGACGGGAGCAGAUCUUGAGAAUGGGGGGAAAAGUCUUGUGCAAUCCACAUUUUUCUUUGAAGUAACUCUACAAAGAAUGCAAUGUUGACUUAAGGAGGGCUCCCAAUGGAUGGCUAAGCCUGCUUAAAGAUCUGCGUAAUCGCUGCUGUGCUCCUGGGCACUGGGCAUGAGUGAGAAGCAGCCGCAUGAAACCGAGAUUGAUGAACAGAGUGAGCUGAAAGCCAUCGAGAAAGAGAAGAAGGUGACAGCCCUGCCCCCCAAGGAAGCGUGCAAAUGCCAGAAAGAGGAUUUGGCCAGAGCGUUUUGUGUGGACUUACACACUGGGCUGUCGGAGUUCUCGGUGACGCAGCGCCGGCUGGCCCAUGGCUGGAAUGAGUUUGUUGCUGACAACAGCGAACCUGUGUGGAAGAAAUACCUGGAUCAGUUUAAGAACCCCCUGAUCCUGCUGCUGCUGGGCUCUGCCCUGGUGAGUGUCCUCACCAAGGAGUAUGAGGACGCCGUCAGCAUCGCCACGGCAGUGCUUGUCGUGGUCACUGUCGCCUUCAUCCAGGAGUACAGGUCGGAGAAAUCUCUGGAAGAGCUGACCAAGCUGGUUCCUCCAGAAUGUAACUGCCUAAGAGAAGGAAAACUCCAGCACCUGCUUGCUCGAGAACUGGUUCCUGGUGAUGUCGUAUCUCUCUCGAUCGGAGACCGGAUCCCUGCAGACAUCCGACUCACUGAGGUCACGGACCUCUUGGUGGAUGAAUCCAGUUUCACCGGGGAAGCCGAGCCAUGUAGUAAAACAGACAGCCCCUUGACAGGCGGUGGGGACCUCACCACCCUCAGCAACAUCGUCUUCAUGGGGACCCUGGUGCAGUAUGGGAGGGGCCAGGGGGUCGUGAUUGGAACAGGGGAAAGCUCUCAGUUCGGAGAAGUGUUUAAGAUGAUGCAGGCUGAAGAGACACCUAAAACUCCUUUGCAGAAAAGCAUGGACAGGCUAGGAAAGCAACUGACACUCUUCUCCUUUGGCAUAAUCGGUCUCAUCAUGCUCAUUGGCUGGUCGCAAGGGAAACAACUCCUGAGUAUGUUCACGAUCGGGGUCAGCCUGGCUGUGGCGGCCAUUCCAGAGGGUCUGCCCAUCGUCGUCAUGGUGACGCUGGUCCUGGGAGUGCUGCGGAUGGCCAAGAAGCGGGUCAUCGUGAAGAAGUUACCCAUCGUGGAGACUUUAGGUUGCUGCAGCGUUCUCUGUUCUGACAAGACGGGGACUCUGACUGCCAAUGAAAUGACAGUGACCCAGCUUGUAACGUCAGAUGGGCUUCGUGCCGAGGUCAGCGGAGUUGGGUAUGACGGUCAAGGGACUGUGUGUCUUCUACCAUCCAAGGAAGUCAUUAAGGAAUUUUCCAAUGUCUCAGUGGGAAAGUUAGUGGAGGCGGGCUGUGUUGCCAACAAUGCGGUCAUCAGAAAGAACGCCGUGAUGGGGCAGCCCACCGAGGGUGCAUUGAUGGCCCUGGCGAUGAAGAUGGACUUAAGUGAUAUUAAAAAUUCAUAUAUAAGAAAAAAAGAGAUUCCAUUCAGUUCAGAGCAGAAGUGGAUGGCGGUGAAAUGCAGUCUGAAGACUGAGGAUCAGGAAGACAUUUACUUCAUGAAAGGGGCCUUGGAAGAGGUGAUCCGCUACUGCACCAUGUACAACAACGGGGGCAUCCCCCUGCCGCUGACGCCCCAGCAGAGGUCAUUCUGCCUGCAGGAAGAGAAGAGGAUGGGGUCGCUCGGUUUGCGGGUGCUGGCCCUGGCUUCUGGGCCCGAGCUGGGGCGGCUGACGUUUCUCGGUCUUGUGGGCAUCAUUGACCCCCCGAGAGUUGGCGUGAAGGAAGCAGUCCAGGUUCUCUCCGAGUCUGGUGUGUCUGUGAAGAUGAUAACGGGGGAUGCCCUGGAGACGGCCUUGGCCAUAGGAAGAAACAUCGGCCUGUGCAACGGGAAGCUGCAAGCCAUGUCCGGGGAGGAGGUGGACAGCGUGGAGAAGGGCGAGCUGGCCGACCGCGUGGGGAAGGUGUCCGUGUUCUUCAGGACCAGCCCAAAGCACAAGCUCAAAAUCAUCAAGGCUCUGCAGGAGUCAGGGGCGAUCGUGGCCAUGACUGGGGAUGGGGUGAACGACGCAGUGGCCCUGAAGUCUGCAGACAUUGGGAUCGCCAUGGGGCAGACAGGGACGGACGUCAGCAAAGAGGCCGCCAACAUGAUCCUGGUGGAUGAUGACUUCUCAGCCAUCAUGAAUGCAGUGGAGGAAGGCAAGGGUAUUUUUUACAACAUCAAAAACUUUGUCCGAUUCCAGCUGAGCACGAGCAUCUCCGCCCUGAGUCUCAUCACUCUGUCCACCGUGUUCAACCUGCCCAGCCCCCUCAACGCCAUGCAGAUCCUAUGGAUCAACAUCAUCAUGGAUGGGCCACCGGCGCAGAGGAGUUCCCAGAAAACUGAAGUGUGUUGCACUGCAGUGAGACUGGGAGUAGAAGGCAGAGGAGAAAGUACCUGGGCCGGCAGAGCUGGCUUGGGGGUAGAGCCCGUUGACAAAGACGCCUUCAGGCAGCCACCACGGAGUGUGCGGGACACCAUCCUCAGCAGAGCCCUCAUCCUGAAGAUCCUCAUGUCCGCGGCCAUCAUCAUCAGCGGGACCCUCUUUAUCUUCUGGAAGGAGAUGCCUGAAGACAGAGCAAGCACUCCCCGCACCACGACGAUGACGUUCACUUGUUUUGUGUUUUUCGAUCUCUUCAACGCCUUGACCUGCCGCUCUCAGACCAAGCUGAUAUUUGAGAUCGGCUUUCUCAGGAACCACAUGUUCCUCUACUCCGUCCUGGGGUCCAUCCUGGGGCAGCUGGCGGUCAUUUACAUCCCCCCGCUGCAGAGGGUCUUCCAGACGGAGAACCUGGGAGCGCUUGAUUUGCUGUUUUUAACUGGAUUGGCCUCAUCCGUCUUCAUUUUGUCAGAGCUCCUCAAACUAUGUGAAAAAUACUGUUGCAGCCCCAAGAGAGUCCAGAUGCACCCUGAAGAUGUGUAGUGGACCGCACUCCGCGGCACCUUCCCUAAUCAUCUCGAUCUGGUUGUGACUGUGGCCCCUGCCGUGUCUCCUCGUCAGGGGAGACUUUUAGGAGGCCGCAGCCUUCCAUCACCGGAUCAGUUUUUCCUCUUAGGAAAGCUGCAGGAACCUCGUGGGCUCCAGGGACCCAGGCCCACAUCCAUCCAGCGUUCCCGCUGGCUGUGGGACAGACAGGGAGGGGCCUGUACAGAAACACCACACUGUUUAUUAAAUCACAAUGAUUUUUAUUAACCAUGUCUAACUACGUAUCUGUGCCACAGCUUGCAGUGAGGCAGGCCACUCGUGGCAGAUACAAGGGGCUCCUGAGAGGCAGUGGGUAGGAUGGUCACACUCUGCCCAUUGCCCUCCUGGAGGCCCCAUUUCCUCAUCAUAAAAUGAGGGACUUUUAAAUAAAGUGCUAUGCCGGGGGAUAAUUA